GGUUUUUGUUGAGGAGAGCGCGGCCGGAGAGCAGAGCUCCGGGACCCAGGUGACCGGGAAAGCAGGCAGCCCCAGCGGCGGGAGCAGCCGGCAGCAGCCCAGGCCCGGGGACUGGGGUGGGGGUGGGAGGGGGGCUGAGGGGAGGACCUGAAGGGGGGCGGCAGGGCAAAAGGGACCCCUGGAGCCCUGCCGCCAUCAGAGAUCAAGCAUCUGGCAUCAGGGAUCUUCGGACCCAGCAGAAGGAUCCGCCACAGGGGAGGUGUCCUCCCAGGGAAGCCAACGAGAGAUUCACCUGCCCCACAUCAGGAGUGGGCCCCCCUUACUGACGCUGCUGGCAACCAUAGCAGGCCCCUUAACCCCUCAGUCUCCUCCCCAUCACCCUCCUCAGGCCCUUUCCCCGCCUCCAGCUCUCAUCUCAACUCCCAGUUCCCAGCCCUCUAAGCCCUAGCACCCCCGGCUACCACCUAACCCUCCAGGUCUUGGCCAUACUCACCCCCAUCCUGGGACAUUUGCCAGAUCUCUGGGAGGGAGAUCGUUUGUUUAGGCGAUGCCCCCUGGUGGCAUGACAGCGUCUGCCUAGACCCCUGACCCCUAGCACUCAACUCCCUGGGCCUCCUUUGUGUGAAGAGCCGCCCCUCUGCUUAGCAGCGUGGUUGGGGGCCAAAGGGAAAGCCAGCCCCAGCUGGGCCCCCGGGCCCCACCACUUAUCUCCUUGCUGGGCAGCUCCCCUUGGCCUUUGGGCCUCUCCCUGCUCCCCUCGGCCCCUCCUCCUGGGCCGCCUCAAUGAAGGAGCCGGAUGCCAUCAAGCUGUUUGUGGGGCAGAUCCCGAGGCAUCUGGAGGAGAAGGACCUGAAGCCCAUCUUCGAACAGUUUGGUCGGAUCUUUGAGCUGACUGUCAUCAAGGACAAGUACACCGGGCUGCACAAGGGUGAGGGGUCGGGCAGGCUGAAGAGGCUUCGGGGUGGGCUGGGAGGCUGGGGGAAGUUAAGCCAGGCUGGAGGGGUGGAGCGGCUGGGAAGGGCUGAUGUGGAAGGAGAAGAGUUCAGGCCUGAGGAAAGUGGAUGGAGGAGCUGAAAAAGAACUCAGCUAGAGUGAUCAGGAAACCCCGGUGAAGGACUAAGGAGGGCCUCUUUUGGCUGAAGAGUUGUCAAGACGGCUGCAAAGAUGUGGAUCCCAGACAUAUGGGAUGUGCCUUCCUGACAUACUGUGCCCGGGAUUCAGCCCUGAAGGCCCAGAGCGCCCUGCACGAACAGAAGACGCUUCCAGGGAUGAACAGGCCGAUCCAGGUCAAGCCAGCCGACAGCGAGAGCCGAGGAGAAGACCGGAAGCUCUUUGUGGGGAUGCUAGGGAAGCAGCAGACAGAUGAGGACGUCCGGAAGAUGUUUGAGCCCUUCGGGACCAUCGACGAGUGCACUGUGCUCCGGGGGCCAGAUGGCACCAGCAAAGGCUGCGCCUUCGUGAAGUUCCAGACCCACGCUGAGGCCCAGGCGGCCAUCAACACCCUUCACAGCAGCCGGACCCUGCCAGGUGCCUCGUCCAGCCUGGUGGUGAAGUUUGCUGACACUGAGAAGGAGCGAGGUCUCCGCCGCAUGCAGCAGGUGGCCACCCAGUUGGGCAUGUUCAGCCCCAUCGCCCUCCAGUUUGGAGCCUACAGCGCCUACACCCAGGCCCUGAUGCAGCAGCAGGCGGCCCUGGUAGCGGCUCACAGUGCCUACCUCAGCCCCAUGGCCACCAUGGCUGCCGUGCAGAUGCAGCACAUGGCUGCCAUCAAUGCCAAUGGCCUCAUCGCCACCCCCAUCACCCCAUCCUCAGGAACCAGCACCCCUCCUGCCAUCGCUGCCACGCCUGUCUCUGCCAUUCCGGCUGCCCUGGGCGUCAACGGCUACAGCCCGGUGCCCACCCAGCCCACUGGGCAGCCUGCCCCUGAUGCUCUGUAUCCCAACGGGGUUCACCCCUACCCAGCCCAGAGCCCCGCGGCCCCCGUGGACCCCCUGCAGCAGGCCUACGCGGGGAUGCAGCACUACACAGCAGCCUACCCAGCAGCCUACAGCCUGGUUGCACCUGCGUUCCCGCAGCCUCCAGCCCUGGUCGCCCAGCAGCCCCCACCACCACCUCAACAGCAGCAGCAGCAGCAGCAGCAGCAACAGCAGCAGCAGCAAAGAGAAGGCCCUGAUGGCUGCAACAUCUUCAUCUACCACCUGCCCCAGGAGUUCACUGACUCAGAGAUCCUCCAGAUGUUUGUCCCCUUUGGCCACGUCAUCUCAGCCAAAGUCUUUGUUGACCGAGCCACCAAUCAAAGCAAAUGUUUUGGCUUUGUGAGUUUCGACAAUCCGGCCAGUGCCCAGGCUGCCAUCCAGGCCAUGAAUGGCUUCCAGAUCGGCAUGAAGCGCCUCAAAGUCCAGCUAAAGCGGCCUAAGGAUGCCAACCGGCCCUACUGAGGGCCCCCAGGUCUGGAGAUCCCAGAGGAAGGGGCGCCUCACACCCUCUUCCCACGACUGGCCCCGGCCCUCUCCGCACACCUGCCCUGGGCCUUGACUGGGUUCUGGGGCAAACGCUGCUUCGUGGCCCCCGGGGGCACAAGACACCGGCCCCUCCCACCCCCCUGCCUCUCUGAAGGGCCAUGGCUAUGCUUCCCUGGCUCCAAGGGCCCAUUUCCUCCUAGAUGCCCUUUUGGCCUUUGUGAGGGAGCGAGGAACAGGCUCGAAGGCUCCGGGGUAUCUGCCUUCUGCUGGGCUCCUGUGACAGGCCUUCUGUACCCAGCGUUUGUACUUGCCUCCCCCAACAGUGGGCCUGUUCUACCCGUGCAGGCCCCAGGAGAGCCGCAGGGGCCUGCCACACACUCCCAGCUCACCCUCACCCCAGCCUCUUCCCCACAUUAGGGGUUUCUUGGAAGCUGGCUCUCACUCCCCUCCACCCUCAGCUAGAGGUAGGAUAUCCCUGAUUCCUGGGCUCCCAGCCCUAAAACUCACUGCCUCCCCCAAGGGCCCCCUCUAAGGAGGGUGUGGGGGAGCCCUGAGGGCUGCCUCUCUGCCAGUCAGCCACAGAGACCCUCCUCCUUUCACGAGGAAAAGACCUUCCCCUGAACCCCUAAAAAUGUUUACAGUCUCUGCUGGUUCCCUCUGUGUAAAUACCACUACCACCCGUGCGUUAUCCAGCCCGCCCGGCCUGGCCCGGACGCUGCCAUCUCUCUUUCUGGGAGUUUAGACAAUGUUGCCCUUGGAUUUUUUUCUCUCUCUUAAUUUCUCCCUUUGCUUUGGGGGGUAAUUGGGUAUUGGGAGGAGGGGUGUGGGGAGGGGUCAAGGGGUUUAUUACCUGAUCAUUUUCUUUAGGAAGAGGUUUUAGGGAAAAGAAAAUGGGGUGGGGGUGGGGGUGGUAAGGGGAGACCGGGGAGUCAGUUUCAGACAGUUCUCUAUGCUUAACUUAUUUAUUUAUUGCAUUUUACUUUUAAAGAGUUGGUCUUUUCUGUCUAAAUAAAGAAAAAAGUUUAAAAGCAUCAAAUAAGAGUCUUGGAAGGUUGAGGGUAGGGGAUUGUUCCCUACCCACACUGGGAAGGGGGAGGGAGGUAGAGAAUGAGGUUUGAGAGAGAAAAUCCCAUCAGGGAAGGCCGGGCCCUUGCUUUUGAGCAGCAUCCAGGCCUUGUUCAUGGCUUCAUGAUCCUGUCCUUCAGCCCUUCUUUGGGGCUUAAUUCUGGAAUGUCCUGCAGAGUUCGGCACAAGGAGAUCUCCCCUGUCGGGGGCUCUCCCCUGUAUCCAGCUCUGUCCCUCUGAAGGCUGAGGACUUGCAGUCUCACAUCUGGACCUCCAUUUCUGCACAGAGGCCAGUGUGGAUACUGGGAGCCAGUUGUGACACCACCAUUUACUAACCACUGCUCCAUAUGUGAUUCUGUUCCAAGUCCUUAUUGUGCAUUUCCUCAUUUUACCUCCUAACAACCUUGUGAGGCAGGCUAUAGUUUAUUUAUUUUACUUAUUUACUUUGAAACAGGGUCUCACUCUGUCACUCAAGCUGGAGUGUGAUGGUGAGAUCAUAGCUCACUGCAACCUUGAACUCCUGGUUCAGGGGAUCCUCCUGUCUCAGCCUCCCAAGUAGUUAGGACUAUAAGCGGCUGCACCACCACGCCCAGCUCAUUUUUAAAAAUGGUGUUUUUUUUUGUAGACAGGGUCUUGCUAUGUUGCCCAGGCUGGUCUCGAACCCCUGGGCUCAAGCAAACCUCCUGCCUUGGCCUCCCGAAGUGCUCAGAUUACAGGCAUGAGCCACCACGCCCAGCCUAGGUAGGAUAUAAUUUUAUAGAUGGGAAAAGGAGGCUUGGAAGGUUAACUAACUUCCCUGGAGUCACAAAGCCAGUAAGGCAUGGCUGUAGGAGUUGAACCCAGUUUGUCAGAUUCCAAAGCCCAUGAUGUUCUCUUCUUACCUGUUCUUUGACCUGAGGCAAAGAUCCCAAGAAGUAGCAAGCAGGCUUAGGAGUGAGUCCUUCAGGUAGAGGGUGGACUGCAUAAGCCCUAAGUCCCUCCACUUCCUAGAUUCUUCUCUGUGAGCUGCUUUAGGGCAGGCUCAGGAUCACACAGGUGUCUUCUUUGACUUCAUAGAACAUGUGCUUCUAGGCUGCUACCCCACCCUCUGUCUUCAUCAUUAGUAAGCAGCACCACUAGGUACCUACUCAAGCCAAAACUUGGAUUACACCCUUUCUCUCAUGUCUCCUCCCCAAUCCAACUGCAAAGCCCUACCAAGUCUACCUCUAAAGUAUUCAGCUGAUUUACUUACUCAUGUCUCUGCAUCUCCACAGCCAUCAACACUGUCCACGUCACAUUGCUCUCAUCUGUCUCCAUGUUUCUUUUCCUGCUCUCCUACAAUUUGUUCUCCCAAGAAGCCAAGAGUCAUCUUUUAAAAGUUAAUUCACCAACAUUUACUACCCAGUCUGCUUUGUCCAGCACUGUAUCCUGGUCACCCUAAACAGUGCCCCAAAUAUUAGACAUUGCUUAGUAAAUAAGAAAUGACUGUUGGACAUCUAUACUGGACUUCCCAUCCAUAUCUACAUCAUCAUAGGGCCAAUGCUAAAACUUUCUCCCAUAAAGUCCUGACUCAUAUAUUUCUAUUUUCUAGUCACAUAGACAGAAAACCUCAAGAGUUUUUAGUACUUUCGCAUAAACUCAAUGGUAUUAAAUCAUUUAAGAUUUCACUUCCACAAACUUUCUCAUAUCAUUUCCCUCUUUUCAAUUAUCACUGCCUACACUUAUUAACUGAGUAAUCAUAGCAAUUUCCUAAUUGGUCCUUCUGUCUAUGUUCUGAAGCAUCAAUCUUUCUAAACUGCAGCUAAUAAAAAACAAAACUUCUCUGCUGCUGUUUUUUGUUGUUUUUCAUAGAACACCUCAGCCUGGCAUUCAAGGCUCUUCGAAGCCUUACUUUCCACUUCAUUCCUACACAUACCCAAAUAGAACUAUUCAUUGUUCUCUAGGCAAGUUUGGUCCCUUUUCUCCCAUGUCUUUUCAUUCCCAGUUACUACAGUGUCUGGCACAUAACGGCUCAAUAAAUGUUUGUUGAAUGCCUUCUUGUUGAAAUCCUUCUCACACUAAAACAGUUCACCUUAAACACUACUUUCUUCAUGAAAAUCUUAACGGCCCUCAUCCACAGGUCUUUCUCCUUCCUUUUCUAGUCCUUAUGGCACUUAAACCUUUCACUGCUGUGUAUCAUGGCCAUGCGUAAGUGUCUCAUUCUUCUGUGAGCCUGUAAGCUGGCAGAAAUGUUUCUUUCUUUGCUUUUGUGUCUGUUGCAGUAUCUCAAACAAUCUCCCCACCCCACCCCCAACAGCAGAUACCUAAUAAAUGUUUGACUUUAACCACUGUAA